AGUCAUCCUAUCUCAUAUGGACUGAGAAAGACCUGUGAGAAAUUAAUAGUAAUUCUUUGCACAGACUGGAAAGUUCUGAAGUUGCAACUUUGGAACGAUGUGUGUUUCUCUUAUUACUUGCACACCUUGUAUCAUUUGAUUCUAACUUUGUCAGGUAGAGGGAGGCCAGUGUUGUUAAUUAUCCCUUUUUUAGAUGAGGAAAGUGUGGGUCCCUCACCAGGGCACACUGACUGGCCCACUGGGGUCCUGUGGUGAGUGGCCAUGGGGGAAUGUCAGGCCCAAGCAGUGUGGUAUGUGGGAUGGCCCAGCUCCAGAGCAGCAGGUCCUGGACUUCAUUCUGGCUUUGUAUUGAUGUUAUUGAAGUCCCCUCGUCCCUCAAAACAUUUGCCUUCACGCAGUGACUGCUUGGCUUUCCAUUACAAUGGGAGCUGGAUUCAAACAGUAUCAUUCUGAACUUUUUAUUUUUUGAGACGGAGUUUCGCUCUUGUCACCCAGGCUGGAGUGCAAUGGCACGAUCUUGGCUCAUCACAACCUCCCCCCUCCUGGGUUCAAGUGAUUCUCCUGCGUCAGCCUCCCGAGUAGCUGGGAUUACAGGCAUACACCACCAUGCCCGGCUGAUUUUGUAUUUUUAGUAGAGAUGGGGUUUCUUCAUGUUGGUCAGGUUGGUCUUGAACUCCUGACCUCGGGUGAUCUGCCUGCCUCGGCCUCCCAGAGUGCUGGGAUUACAAGUGUGAGCCACCGCGCCUGGCCCCAUUCUGAACUUUAUUAAUGGCUCAUGUAAAUCUGAACUUCAACAAUCUUGAUUCUUACGAGGAAUAGAGAUGAGUCUCCUUUUCCUUUGCUACUAAUUUGGCUAAAAUUGCAUAGCGAAGUUUUAAACUCUCCUGACCUCUGUUUUGUCUUCUGUGAAACUAGGGGUUGCCUGUAAUGUACUUUCACAACCUUUUAUAGCCCCAACUUUCGCUGUGUUAAAAUUGAGAUGGGACAGGUCCUUGAUUAUUAGGGAUUUUUUUUUCUUCAAAGUGGCAUGGGAUGAACUGAUCUAUGUGUAAAUUGAUGUUGCUGUUGCUUUUCUCUGAGUGUAGUUAGGAGGGCUGGAAGUAUAUGGGUGCAGAGAUGUAGAAAGGCUACGUUGUUCAUCCUGCCACCGACAGGUCAGACUGUUCUCCUGGCUAUGUUUUCACUCAGUUGUGUACCUGCAGUUCAUACCUACAUAGGACCAGCCAUGGGCCAGGCACUGUGCUGGGUGCCGUGGGAAAACCACAGCAAACCAGACAAACACCAGCCUUUGGGGAGCCUGUAAACCAGUGUGGAGAUCUUACAAGCUCACAGUCCACUGUAAUCUUAAUUAACAAGUAUGGAAAAUAACUUUCGCCAUCUCUGGGUGGGGGAAGCACAUAUGGGAAGUCCCCCUCUAACCUCUAACCCAACCCCCAAGGCCAGGCAGAAUUCAUUUGAAGCAUUCUGGAGGAUAAUAUUUUCUUCAAGAUCCUCAGAAGCUCUUCAGUGCACAGGCAACUCCCAGAUACUGGAAUUGUCACCUGAGCUGAGACAUUCCACAUGCCAGUUGUAAGCCAGGUCUCCACCACAGCUGGGGUGAAGCACCUCUAUUCUCUCAUGCCAGGGUGGGUGUUAUUAUUCCAGGGCCUGGAUGAAGCUCAGUUAGUUUGCUUAGGAUGAACACAUGAUUUGUGGGUCAAUUUUCAGGUAAUGUGAACUCUACUUACAUGUUGUUUAUUGCUUGAGAGCUUUAUCUCUUAAAAAUGAGUUAAACUACUUGGCGCUUUGAGUGGAAUGCAGGUCUCAGGUAGCACACUAAUACUUCCUUAUUUUUUUUUAAUUGAUAAUGGCAUAAAGCCAUUAUGCCAUCACAUUUGAUAUAGAGAUGUAAGUAAUUGAAUCACAUUACUUCUCUUGGAUUAGUAAUGAAUAUUGCACAUCAAUCCUGUGCACACAUUUUACAGGUUUGUUUUAUCCUAUUGAUGGUUUCAUUUGAACUGUGUUUGGAAAUUUAGUUUAUUUCUUACUCCAUUGUAGAUGUUUGUUUUUGUUGUUUUUGUUUUUUUUUUUUUUUGAGACAGAGUCUCGCUCUGUCACCCAUGCUGGAGUGCAGUCGCUUGAUCUCGGCUCACUGCAACCUCUGUCCCCGGGUUCAAGCAGUUCUUCUGCCUCAGCCUCUCGAGUAGCUGGUACUACAGGUGCGUACCACCAUGCCCGGCUAAUUUUCGUAUUUUUAGUAGAGACGGGGUUUCACCAUAUUGGCCAGGCUGGUCUUGAACUCCUGACCUUGUGAUCCACCCGCCUCAGCCUCCCAAAGUGCUGGGAUGACAGGUUUGAGCCACUGAGCCCGUCCCGUUUUUGUAUUUUUUAAAUGCAGUGUUUGAAAUUCUUGACUUCUACACAGUAGUCAAGACUGAUACUUCUACCCAGUACCCAAAUUACUGUACUGCUCUGACAGUAAGUUGUUACAAAACUAUUUUCCAAAGGUUGGAACUGAUUUCAGGGUUUACAUUUAAGCUUUGUUUAACAUCUGAAACUGAAUUAAUGCUAGCAUUCAAAACUAGUAAAAUCAUUAUUAGUGAUUCGUCCUCUAUUUGACACUGAACCAGCAGACAUUUCCCUUAGCUUUUGGUGACAUGGAUUAAAGUAAAAUGGUUUUGGUGAUUUACUAUAGUUAAUUAGUGAUAGACUAUAAUUAAUGCUUAGUGUUUUGAAUGAACUUAAUUUGCAAAUAAUGAUAAUUUAAGAUCUGAGUUUGAUAAAAUUUUAAAGGUUGAUCGAAUACCUAGAUUCCUGGUUCUUGGGCCUUCAGAAGGAGAGAAUUUCACGUGUUAAGUCCUUAUUUGGUCUUAUUCAAGGGAGCAAGAUUUUUUGUUUGUUUAUAAACACAUGCAGUAUAUCGUUUUACGUAUUCAAGUACACAUAGUACGUUCUCUGGGGAAAGCAGAAAAUUGUAUUGCAUUUCAGCCAUGUAAUACCCUCACGUUCGUGUAUUAAGCUGAUCAAUAGGGGUAUUUAUUUCCUUUUGUUGAGCACAGUGUUUUAACGUUUCCAAAGUGUAAUUUGUUAUUGUUGAAAGUCAACCAUGUUACCCUAUGCAUACAGGCUUUUAUAUAAUAAAACAUAUGGUAUAUAUUUUUAAGUAAGCGCUUAAUUUUAGAAUAGAUUUUAAAUUUACAGAAAAAGUUUCAAAGAUAAUACAGAGAAUUCUGAUAUAAACUGUGUCUACUUUCCCCUGUGAUUCACAUCUUACGUUACUAUAGUACAUUGGUUACAUCUAAUGAACCAGUAUUGGUACAUUAUUGUUAAGUCCAUAGUUUAUUUGCCCUGACAUCCUUUUUCUGUCCCAGGAUCCCAUCCAGGGCACGUUUCCUUUAGUCUCCGUAGCGCCUCUGAUCUGGGACAGUUUCUUAGACUCGCCUUGUUUUUAAUGGCUUGACAGCUUUGAGGAGCAAAACUGCUUUUCAGGUGUUUUGUAGACUGUCCCUCAGUUGAGAGUUGUCAGAUGUUUUUUCAUGAUUAGUGUAGAGUUACCGGUUUGGGGAGGAAGGCCACCGAGGUAAUGUGCCAUUUUGUAUCAAGGGUCCAUGUGAUCAGCGUGGCUUAUGAUGGUUGAUGUUGAUCUUGAUCACCUGGCCCAGGUAGUGUUUGUCAGGGGACUCCACUGUCAAGUGACUCCACUGUCAAGUGACUCUUUUCCCUUCUUUCCAUACUGCUGCAGUCUUUGGAAGGAGGUCAUUUAAGGAAGAGGGAGUUCAGCUGUACCUCCUGUAGGGGUUGUAUUUACAUUAGUUAUUUAGAAUUCUAUCUGACAGAUUUAUCUAUUCUCCCAAAAGGGACCAAGAUUUUCAGUGGGGAUAGAAGGCACUGUGGCACAGACAGCCCCUUGGCACUGUUGCGGAGGAGGUGAUAGGAUAGGAUGGUGCCCCAGCAUGGGGUUUCCAGAAUGUGGUCCUGGGCUGUGGAGAAAUGCAAAUUCCGGGGAACUGCCUGACUUCCCGCGUGGGAUAGGUUGGUCUGGAAUUCUUCCUGUUGCACGAGUUCCCCAGGUGAUUCUGAUGCAUAUUCAAAGUUGAGAGCCUCUGCUGUGGAUUAGCACUUGAACCCCAGGUGUGCCGGCCAGGAGUCAGGCCCUCACCUCCAUCCUUGCCGUUCACACCUCUUCCCUGCUGGUGGCACCUAGCUCUAAGGCUCCCCGUGUAACCACUUCUCCCACAGUUUUGACCACCUCUUGGAUCUCUCCAUCUGAGGCUCCCUUUGUAUCAACCAAGGGUCUUUGCUUUCUGGAUAACUUCAUCCUUCUUUUGGUGGGCCCAGAGUUCCAGUGAAGGGAGAAACCAGUUACAGCUGAGAACCCUAUUGUGGAAAGGCCAGUCAGGGCCAGAGUAGGGAGGUCCCUAGAUGCCAGGCUUCUCUGAAAAUGGUUUUGUCACAUGUGAGAGAGAGAGAGAGGCAGAGACACCGAGACCCCACGUGGACUGUGUUCAGGUUUGAGCAAAUAAAAAAUCACCGAAAAAUCUUCAUAGUUUCUACAUGUGUCAUGCCUUGCGCUUUGGGACACCCCUAGCUCUUGGGCACAUUCCCUGGUUGAAGUGGGAGGGCAGUGGCCUGAAGAAGUUUCUUUGGGAUUGGGAUCUGGGUGGCCCUCAUCCUGCUUCCGCCUGAGGAAGCCCUGGUCUGUGACUGGGCUCAGGAAGUGGUCCCGACCCAGUGUCUGAGGAAGGCAUUCUCCUCUCAUAGAUGGGGGCCAGAGUCUGCUGUGAGGCCAUGCUGGUGUGCCUGCCCGCCCACCCUACUGGGCCUCUUCUGGGCAGCAGGGUUGUGCCCUACCCGGGUGCUGGGAGGUUUGGGUGUGUAUGGGAGCGGUGGUAUGGACGGGGCAGGCGUUGGCUCAGAAGCUGGCGUGGGGAGGGUCUUGAAGUGGUCAUUUUAACUCCUGGCUGACUGACUUCCAGAGAAUCUUUUUUUGGGAGGGAGAAGAGUGGCUCACCUUUCUCUUGGGUACAGAAAAAGUCAGAAUUAAGGCCAUUAGCCUGUUUCUCUUUCUGGUCACUGCCUUCUCCCUCCUAGUGAUGGGACGAUUCCAGGCUUGGGUGGAAGGCCAGGUGGGGGGACACUACUUCCUGCUCCACCCUUCCCAAACCAUUAUACACAGAUGAGAGAGACUCUGUUGUAUUCAUUCACAUAGAUAUAAUUUAUAAUAAUGCAUUUUGUUUAUUAAAAAAUGACUGGGCCAGGCAGAGUGGCUCAUAGUGGCUCAUGCCUGUAAUCCCAGCACUUUGGGAGGCUCAGGUGGGAGGAUUGCUUGAGCCCAGGAGUUCAAGACCAGCCUGGGCAACAUGGCGAAACCCUGUCUCUACAAGAAAUACAAAAAAAUGAGCUGGGUAUGGUGGCAAGUGCCUGUAGUCCCAGCUACUUAGGAGACUGAGGCAGGAGGAUCACUUGAGCCUGGGAGGUCCAGGCUGCAGUGAGCCGUGAUCAGGCCCCUGUACUCCAGCCUAUAUGACAGUGAGACCAAAAAAGACUGAAUACAGACAUGUGCGCUGACCCUUUUGAACAUUAUUUUCUUUUCAAUCUCUGCCUCUGUGUUACAGUUUAUGUUUUCUCUUUUGUCCUGCGGAUUUUUGAUACAUUUUAAAAAUAUCUUGUCCUUUUUCUAAGUUUUUGCGUUGACUACAGUUGCAAGUGUGGGUUUUGGUGGCUUUCUGUAGAUGAAUCACUUGACCUGAAAACAAGGACUUUCGCUUUGCUAGAAAAUUAAGGACAGAGUUUGUGGAAUGCACUGCUCUUGGGUUUUCCUUAGAAGAAGCUUGUGAGAAGCACAGUUUCUGUGCGUAAGAGUGGGCUUAAACCAGGUGAUCUCCGAAGAUUUCCUUCAACUCUCAAGUUGAAAGAGGCCUUGCCGAGGAAACAGGCAGCUAAUGGGCAGAGCAUCAAACCAGGGGGGGUCUAGGUCCAGGCCCGGGCGCUUCCUGCUGUCAGACUGCCUCCUCACAUCAGCAGGCAUUCCUGGGAUUCACAGCAACAAAAGAGCCCUCUGCUUUGAAAGGGGUUCAGUCUGUCUCUUCUGUAGUCUGGACUCUGGAAUCUAGAGAUUCGCUGAAGCUCAUGUCCCAGGGUCUUGACGUAGUGUGAAGUUCUGAGUGAUUUCCUAAAGACGGUGUCCUGAACCAUGGGCCUGUGGUGGUGAGUGCAUGGAGGAUAUCUGUGAACUUUGGGGUGGGAAAAAACAUCCUUAUUUCCACCAGCUUUUCACUGAAAUUCAGUAUUUCCUUCCUGCAUGAAUGUAGGUAGCACAGCCCAUAGCAUUUACAGUCAUCAGAGAAAUGGUCACUAUUUUCCUGUUACAUAAUAGUGAUGCACGUGUGUUGAAAGAGUGACUGCUUUUAUCAUUGCUCUCAAAUUAUGGUUGUUAUUAGCACUGCUGCUACCCUCUCGUUUGGUGUGUUAAUAAGGAAAUACGUAGAUUACUAUGUCUCAAGUUUGUUUUUAAGUAAUAUAUUAAUAACUGUGUUCCACAUAGUUGCAUAAAAUGAAAAUCACUUAAAAGCAACCUGAGGCCAGGCGCAGUGGCUCACGCCUGUAAUCCUAGCACUUUGGGAGGCCGACGUAGGCGGAUUGCCUGAGCUCAGGAGUUCGAAACCAGCCUGGGCAACACAGUGAAACCCCGUCUCUACUAAAGAAUACAAAAGAAUUAGCCAGGCGUGGUGGUAUGUGCCUGUAGUCCCAGCUACUCAGGAGGCUGAGUCAGGAGAAUUGCUUGAACCCAGAAGGCAGAGGUUGCAGUGAGCCGAGAUCAUGCCACCGCACUCCAGCCUGGGCGACAGAACGAGACUCUUGUCUCCAAAAAAAACAAAACAAAAGCACCCUGAGGAGGAGUCCCUAGCCCUCACCAUUCUGCCAAGGGGAGAGCGGGACCUCGCCAGGGACCAGGUGUCACUGCGUCCUCUGAUGACCGAGCUGCUGGGACCGAGGCUGCUGGCCAGAGACAGUCUACACAGGCAUUGCAGAAAAGUAGCUCAAUUUUGCUGCCUAACAGAACUCUUUCCAGUCAUGCAGUAACGACAAAACAUGCCCCAAGUGGGUAAAAUGAAAACCUGUUCUCAAAAGAGAAUAUAGAAAGAAUUUUAUUUAAAUUGGAUAAAAGCCUAGUUGUUGUUUUUAUAAAUUUUAUUUAAUUAAGUUGUCACAGUGGGAAAUAUUCAAUUUGUUAGUUGAAAAAAAUGUAAAAUUGUGUUCUGGGAUCUGUGAUUAUUUACUGUUACAGCAGUGGGGUUGGGGUUGGGUUGUGCAUUGGGAACUUAGGGGUUUAUAAUAACUUCCAGUAUCAGGACAGUGUAAAUGACUUAAAAUCUCUUGUGUGAAAAAGUUUGACUUUCUGAUUCUCAGCCGUGUUGUGGCAAAAUGGUCCCUGGAGUUUUUGACCCUGUGUUUAAAGAAAUAUGCUAUAAAAUAAAAAAUAAUUUGGAAGAAGAAUUGGCUCAGACAUUACUUUCAUUGUGCCUUCUUGCAUGUGGAACUAUAAAUACCAGCUGCUAGAAGUUCCCUUACGAUGAUGGACUGUGUGAAGGUACAUUCUUAAAGUAUUCAUGUGUCAAUAAUAAUAGCUGAUAUUUAUUGAGCACUUAACGUGGCUGAGCAUUUCAUAUGUGUUGCCUAAUUUAGUCCUCUCUACAACCCCACGAGGCUGCCCUCAGCCCCGUUUAACAGAUGAGGUAGCUGAGAUGGAGAAGCUAAGCAAUUUGUCCGAGUGCUAGUCCUGGCAGCUUCGCUUUGCAGAGCUUUCACGUGGGUGCAUGCUGUUUGCACGCCUGUGCAAUGAUCCUUGGUGUGGGCCACAGCCUUGACCCUGCAGCACCUGCUGGCCUUCAGCACCUGUGGCACCACAGCCUUGACCCUUCAGCACCUUUGCAUCCGCACCCUGCAGGUUAAGGAGAGCCUGUGGGCAGACAUCCCACAUUCUUAAUUAUUUUAGCCCCACAGCUCGAGUGGAAAUGCUUCCUUCUGCAGGGCUGUCUGAGCUCCACAUGUUUAUCGCCGGCCACCCUCCUAGGACUGCAUCCCUGCAGGAGCCUGCAGCCUGCUCUGCUUCGAGGCUCAGCCACAAAGCUGCCUCAAAACCUGAUGGCCUGCCUCAUCUGACUGAGACAGAUUUCAUGUGUUCUUUGUAUACAAGCGACGUCCCAGAUUAUAAUUCUCUGCUGAGAUUUGAGUUGGAUUUGAGGAUUUGGAGAAUCCCUGCAGCUUUGUAACUUCAGAGGUGUAAUUAGCUGAAAACAUCAUCGUUUUGAAGAGUUCUGCGUUUUGCCAGUCACCUCUCAACUGUGUGCCAAAGAAGGACUCCAUGAAAGAUGACAGAAGAAGUUAUUGUGAUAGCCAAGUGGGACUACACCGCCCAGCAGGACCAGGAGCUGGACAUCAAGAAGAACGAGCGGCUGUGGUUGCUGGACGACUCCAAGACGUGGUGGCGGGUGAGGAACGCGGCCAACAGGACGGGCUAUGUACCGUCCAACUACGUGGAGCGGAAGAACAGCCUGAAGAAGGGCUCCCUCGUGAAGAACCUGAAGGACACACUAGGCCUCGGCAAGACGCGCAGGAAGACCAGCGCGCGGGAUGCGUCCCCCACGCCCAGCACGGACGCCGAGUACCCCGCCAAUGGCAGCGGCGCCGACCGCAUCUACGACCUCAACAUCCCGGCCUUCGUCAAGUUCGCCUAUGUGGCCGAGCGGGAGGAUGAGUUGUCCCUGGUGAAGGGGUCGCGCGUCACCGUCAUGGAGAAGUGCAGCGACGGUUGGUGGCGGGGCAGCUACAACGGGCAGAUCGGCUGGUUCCCCUCCAACUACGUCUUGGAGGAGGUGGACGAGGCGGCUGCGGAGUCCCCAAGCUUCCUGAGCCUGCGCAAGGGCGCCUCGCUGAGCAAUGGCCAGGGCUCCCGCGUGCUGCAUGUGGUCCAGACGCUGUACCCCUUCAGCUCAGUCACCGAGGAGGAGCUCAACUUCGAGAAGGGGGAGACCAUGGAGGUGAUUGAGAAGCCGGAGAACGACCCCGAGUGGUGGAAAUGCAAAAAUGCCCGGGGCCAGGUGGGCCUCGUCCCCAAAAACUACGUGGUGGUCCUCAGUGACGGGCCUGCCCUGCACCCUGCGCACGCCCCACAGAUAAGCUACACCGGGCCCUCGUCCAGCGGGCGCUUCGCGGGCAGAGAGUGGUACUACGGGAACGUGACGCGGCACCAGGCCGAGUGCGCCCUCAACGAGCGGGGCGUGGAGGGCGACUUCCUCAUUAGGGACAGCGAGUCCUCGCCCAGCGACUUCUCCGUGUCCCUUAAAGCGUCAGGGAAGAACAAACACUUCAAGGUGCAGCUCGUGGACAAUGUCUACUGCAUUGGGCAGCGGCGCUUCCACACCAUGGACGAGCUGGUGGAACACUACAAAAAGGCGCCCAUCUUCACCAGCGAGCACGGGGAGAAGCUCUACCUCGUCAGGGCCCUGCAGUGACGGCGCCCCGGCCCCACACUCGCCUCCCGGGCCCCACGGUGGAGCUGCCCGCCCGGCCUUGUGGCAGAGGCUCCUCCCGCGGGGACGGCCCCGACGGCUUCUCUGCGAGUCUCUCUUUAUGUUCAGGUCGCUUGGUCGGUUCGUCUCCCAUUUGCCAUCCAGGCCUCACACCCACACUCGAGCCCACCCGGCCGGCCAGCUUUAGAGGAGGGGAGGAGCAGGGCGAGUUCACAUUAUUCCUUUUCCAUCGGAAGUGGCGCUCGUGCAUUCAACUCGUUCCCGCUCAUGGAACCCCUCUUUAAAAAGACGCAGGGCACCUGUGAGCGCAGGAGCGAGCCUAAGGCCACCCAGCGGCAGCGCCCGUGUCCUGGGCACUCAGCGUGCUGGGCAGAGCAGGUGCGAUGGCCCCAGUCCUAGCAGCCCUCGCCCAUGUCCUGUGCCCUUACAUGGCUCCCGGACUGUGCAGGGAGCCGAUACGUUUGCUGAUAGCAAUACUGGAACCACCGGGUGCGAUGGCAGUGAGGAGACUGCCCAGUGCCUUUGGGGCUGUGCUUGCAAUAAAGAAUUUCCUGGAAAGGCAGUCUGCAAAAGAGGGAACCGGUGACUCAGAAAGACAGAUGUUUUGGUAAUUUACCCCAAAUGUGCCAUCCACAUAGUGCUUUUUCCUCUUGCCCUUCGGCUUGUUUGAAUCUCACAAUUAUGUAUUUAAUUCUCAAAGAAAUAUGUAUCUGUAGCCGUUUGUUGACACUAAUACAGAUGAUUAAGGAAAACAGCUGAUCUUUGGGGAAGGGAGCUACCAACACUUUAUACACACACACACGUGCACACACACACACACACACACUAUAUAUAUAUAUAUUAUUUACAGGGAAAUUUUUCAGGGUUUACAAAAGAGUAUGUGAUUGGUAGUAAGAGACACACAGAAUGUUUAUGAAGAAAUUGCAUUUUCUUUUUCCUUUACAUUUGAACUUCUUUAUAGUUUAAAUAUAACGUCUUGAGAUGGCACAUUCCUACGAUUGAAGAAGGGGUCUUGAGAUCCCCUAAACUUGCAUACCCAGUUUUUUGGAUAUUGUAAUAAAAAAAAGUAUUAUGACAA